AUGAGAUGCUUGAGACUCAGAAAUGAACCUAGAAUCCCAGAGCUAUGAGAGGCCACCGUGGUCCCUCAAGAGCCUCCCCACCACCACACCCAUCUUGAGAAAACUGGCCCAAGAGAGUACUGCUGCUGGAAUAACCUUGACCUUCUUGCACAAUGAAGAGACAGAAAAGCAGAAUCAACACGCCUGAAGUGAUGUUUAAUUAAUGAUGAUAAUGGACGGGGAUUUGAGAAAUCUUUUCAUUUUCGCUUGCUAAUAAUAAUUUUAGUCAGAGUUACAAGUAGGGUUCUUGAAAAAAAAACAUAUCUGACGUAUAAAGACAAUGGAUUCAGGGAUACUUGAUCAAAUUGUUUCUGAUGAAUGAGGACCCACACUCUCUGCUGUCACAAACAGGAGGUGGGGCCCAAGAAACAGUGGUGAAAGAUGUUUCAGGUUGAUCUGCAAUGGAUUAUUCACAGCAACAAUGAGGAUGAUACAGUUUCAGCUUUUUCCUCCAGCAAGGCCUUACUGACAACCUACUGUCUGCCCAAUAGUAGGGCUUGCAAAGAUUCUUCUAAUUAUAAAUGGAGCAAAAAAUUCUGACCUUCAAUUUGAAAAUCAUAUACUUACACCUUCUUUUGUUAGCAAUUGCACUUCAUCGAUAUAAGGCUUUAGAAGACAAAAUCCUAGACAUCAUUUGAUUUUUAGAAAAUCCUUCUGAGGAGAUAAAUAUCUGGUUUCAUCACCCAGGAGGCUCAUUAUUCACCUCAUGGAGGUGUGAUGUCUUCAAGACAUUAACAAUGUCAUUCAGUUCAUCCACUUUGAUUCAUACAUGCCCAUUUCAGAAACAUAUCUCUUGUAUAUAAAACUGAAUUUCCUUGAAUGUUUUCAAUUGUUUAUUUGGCAUGCUCAUAAAUGCUGUGAGACACUGGUUAUUGUCAGUCAAACACUUUCAGAUUGUAGAUGCUUCCCGGCAUAUGCUCAGACCAAAACCACUCCCAGGGUCAUAAAUUUUAGACUCCAGGCUCGGCUCAACCUAGGAUGAGAACUGCGGGGCUACAUCAAGCACAGACCUGGAGAAGAAUAAAGUUGCCCUAAAUAAGUUGAGUCUUUGCAAGGGGCCUGUGAGGUAAAUUGGCACUUUAUACUUUCCAGGAAAGGGAGGGAGGGACACAGAGGGACAAAAGGCUCUUUUCUUCAUGGCUCUCCUUAGUUCUGACCCCAGGGUAUUCUAUUUGGGGUUGGAAUAAGACUGUCGCCACAACUGCCACCCCUACCACCAUCCCCACUGCUACUAUCACCAUGGCUGUCACUGCUAGCACCAUCACCAUCAGCCAUCACGGGUACCACCAUUGCCACCAUACUCACUACUUCAGCCACACCACUACCACCACCUCACUCCCUCCACCAUGGCAAUUAGUGCCCCCAUCAUCACCACCGUCACCAUCAGCAUCAUUGUUAGCAUGAAUGAAGCCUUGUCCACUGGCCAGGCCUGGUGUCAGCAGCUUUAUAUGCACUAUCUCAGCUAAUUCCCCUGAAAACUUAUGUCCCCACCACUCCUCUUAGCCUCAUUUCAUUAACACACAUAAGGAUACAGUGACUUGGAGACAUUUCACACCAACAAAGUCAAGUGCCUUGUAAGUGACUUGUCGCAUGUGGGAGGAUCCCUCUGCUCUGCCUUUCCUACCUCCCUAUCCUUCCCCAGAUGGAAUACUUCUCUACCUGCUAACAUAUGGGUUACAGUUCCUUACAGAAUUACAAGAAAGUAACAAAGAAAGAGAGUGAGGAAGAAGCGGGAGAAAGCAGGCAGUAGAGAAAGAGGGAAAUAAAACCUUUUCUUCUACAUUAAGGAUAAAAAUUCAAUGGCAAAUUUCUAAUUUAAGAGCACAUAGUCUUAAGUUCACUCUAAAGUGUAACUGAUUAAGGUCAUAUUCCAUUCCUCCCCCAACACACCUCUCUUGGCAGCUUUUUCCAGGGGAAAAGAAGGAAAAAGUACCAGGGCAUUGAAUGCAUGAAGGGUGAGAGCAGGGGUUGAGGGCACAAGCAAAGGAGAGGCUGGAUGCAGAGAGGAGAAACUGAGCUCCCUUGCCUGCCCAGCCUGCAAAACCGGUUCUGCUGAUGUCACUGGGGAAGAAACAGAAGAUAGAUUUCUAAAGAAGCAGACCCUGAGACAAGGAUUCAGAUGCAAGUAGUUUGCUUUGGAGGUGAUCCCAGGAAACACCAGUAGAGUGAGGAAGUGAGACAGGGAAAACAGGGCAGCCAGUGAAAGAGGUUUGGCUACGGAGGCUGGGUGCAGCUCCAACACCACAGCAAGGGAGAAGCAAAGUUGUUGAAAGAUGGGAAAGUCUUCAGAGUGGUGCGAGAGAAUUGCUGGGAUCCAGAAGUUCGUAUUAGAGAAAUGGACCAAAAAGGCCAAACCUGAGGACACUUUAAACCUGUGCCAGCUUUUAAACAACGACCUUGCCAGCACCGUUGUGAGCUACCCCAGGAGGUUCGUGGGUCUGGGGACGUUGCCCAUGCAGGCCCCUGAGCUGGCGGUCAAGGAGAUGGAGCGCUGUGUGAAAGAGCUGGGCUUUCCCGGGGUCCAAAUUGGCACCCACGUCAACGAGUGGGACCUGAACGCGCAGGAGCUCUUUCCUGUCUAUGCGGCAGCCGAAAGGCUGAAGUGUUCCCUGUUCGUGCAUCCCUGGGACAUGCAGAUGGAUGGACGAAUGGCCAAAUACUGGCUCCCUUGGCUUGUAGGAAUGCCAGCAGAGACCACCAUAGCCAUUUGCUCCAUGAUCAUGGGUGGAGUAUUUGAGAAGUUUCCCAAACUGAAAGUGUGUUUCGCACAUGGUGGUGGUGCCUUCCCCUUCACAGUGGGAAGAAUCUCCCAUGGAUUCAGCAUGCGCCCAGAUCUGUGUGCCCAGGACAACCCCAUGAACCCGAAGAAAUACCUUGGUUCCUUUUACACAGAUGCUUUGGUUCAUGAUCCUCUGUCCCUCAAGCUGUUAACAGAUGUCAUAGGAAAGGAUAAAGUCAUUUUGGGAACCGAUUACCCCUUUCCACUAGGUGAGCUGGAACCUGGGAAACUAAUAGAGUCCAUGGAAGAAUUUGAUGAAGAAACAAAGAAUAAACUCAAAGCCGGCAAUGCCCUGGCAUUUUUGGGUCUUGAGAGAAAACAAUUUGAAUGACUGAAUUUACUACAAAGGCAAACUUUCAAAAGGAUAUCUCAUUUUUGUUUCUAAAUAUGUAUCAACAGGUAUCAACAAAAUCCUAUUUUGAACUAUUUUACUCAGAAAUGAAUGUCCCAAAUAUCCUAAAUUAUUCAUAAUAAAAAUGAUUUGUAAGUGUUUUCAUUCUGAAAA